GCCUGGCGGUUCCAGGGUGCACACCACUCCUCGUAGCAGGUCCCCUGUCUUGUGUGCUGUGUCCCCCCGAGGUAUGCUGGUGCUGGUGGCCCAGGCAGGAGGUGACACUCUCAAAGUGACUGGUCACUACGUAAAAUGUGUCUUUCUUUUGUUUGUUUCCCACCUGCUUUCCGAGCCCCUUUCUCGGACAGUUGACCACGGCAUGUUUGAGAAUUUGAACACAGCCCUCACUCCAAAGCUCCAGGCCAGCCGCUCCUUCCCCCACUUGUCCAAGCCCGUGGCCCCCGGCUCUGCCCCUCUGGGCUCUGGUGAGCCUGGGGGGCCAGGACUCUGGGUGGGCAGCAGCCAGCACCUCAAGAACCUGGGCAAAGCCAUGGGGGCCAAAGUGAAUGACUUCCUGAGGAGAAAGGAGCCCUCCAGCCUGGGCAGUGUGGGUGUGACAGAGAUCAACAAGACUGCAGGAGCACAGCUGGCCAGUGGGACUGACGCGGCUCCAGAGGCUUGGCUAGAGGAUGAAAGGUCAGUCCUGCAAGAAACAUUUCCUCGGCUGGAUCCUCCACCUCCCAUAACCAGAAAGCGAACCCCUCGGGCCCUGAAGACCACCCAGGACAUGCUGAUUUCAUCACAGCCUGUCCUCAGCAGUCUGGAGUAUGGGACAGAGCCAUCACCUGGGCAGGCCCAGGACUCCGCUCCCACUGCCCAGCCUGACGUCCCAGCAGACGCUUCACAGCCAGAGGCCACCAUGGAAAGAGAAGAGAGAGGCAAAGUUCUGCCCAAUGGAGAGGUUUCCCUGUCAGUACCUGACCUAAUCCACAAGGAUAGCCAGGACGAAUCCAAGCUAAAGAUGACUGAGUGCAGAAGGGCCUCCUCCCCCAGCCUUAUCGAGAGGAAUGGCUUCAAACUCAGCUUGAGCCCCAUCAGCCUGGCUGAGUCCUGGGAGGAUGGCAGCCCCCCUCCUCAGGCACGGACCUCCAGCCUCGACAAUGAGGGCCCUCACCCAGACCUGCUGUCCUUUGAAUAGAGCCUCUGCUCUUUCCUGCUGAGCUCUGCCCUUGUCUUCCUGCUGCUUUCUCCUCCACUGCGCACACUGGCCCUGGCCUCAACUCCGCUGUGCCCUUUGUCUUCCUUGUAUGAGGCACCAGCAGAGAGCCAGUCGUCCAUCAUGGGAUUUUGCAGGACUGGAAGUCCUUGAGUAGUUCUAGUUAAAGAGUCUAUCCGCAGAAUGGCUGAAGGACUUGAUGCCGUUUUGAGCCUAAUUUUCUGUAACCUCCUCUGAGUGGGCUGCAGCCCUUGGACAUUAGAGCUCUUCCACUCUUGAGCUUGUCCUGUCUUCUCAGUGAAUUGCAGGGCCACCAGCUCAGGACAAUGGAUCUUACAGGAAUUCUUUUUGCCUGUCCCCUACAUGCGCCUCCUCCCCUGCUGUUCUCCCUCCCACACCCCUGUCCCUUCUCUCUCCUCCUUGAUGGGUCCGAUGCCCCUGGCCUCAGCGGGAGGAAGGCUGGAUGAGGAAUGAUGUGUUUGGCUUGAUGACAGGCCAUGGCCUAGAAAGCCACACACCCUGACCACAGCCCAGCCAUAGCUCCUCUUGGUCCCAGGACAGUGCAGGCCCCUGGUUGCCAUGUUUGCUCUGCCCCUGGGGUGGAGGCCAGAGGAGAUGCUUACCAGGCCUGAGACCUUGAGAGUUCACCCAGGGUUUGAACGCUGCCACCCAGGGUUCCCAAGGUUUCUCCCAUCUGGUCAGAUGUCGAACACAAAAUGUGGGCAUUCUGCACGGAAGGAAAGAUCAGGCUUCUCUUGCUGAGUGUGUGAAGACAGGGAGAGCCAGGCCCCAGCAGAUGCGGCCUAGCACACUCUGAUUUGGUUUUGUGGGGAGGGCCCAGGAACUUGGGGGUGGUCUUGGCAUUCAGAGCUGGUGCUAAAAACCCAGAGCAGAAGCAGGGAGAAGGGAGUGAGGAUGGGACAGAGAAGAGCGACCACUGGGGAUCAGAACAGCUUUUCAGGGGCCACCUUGCAGCCUAAAAUAAUGCCGUUUCAGGGCCUGGGCCUGCUGUGAGAGCCAGAAUGAAGCAUGUACAAGAUUGGAAUGUGAGAAGAACUGUGGGGGGAAACCAGUUUUAAUUAAGUGGAAGUGCUUUGUGCUUGUGCUGAAGUUGCCUGGGCCUCCUGCAGCUCUGGACCUCACUGGAGCGGCCCCGCCCUGCCCUUGCCUGCCUUUCUUUUAUGCUGAUGCUGGUGGGCUUUUUCCUGCUUCAGGAUCCAUGUAAGGGACUGACCAGGUUCAUCCAGCCUUAACUGGUUCCUGCAACCCACUUUUAGGUCUCCCACCAGGGGCCUAUUGUGCUGUCUUCCUGUGACCAGCAGAUCCUGUAAGGGGGUGAUCCUAAUUCUGGGGCUCUUUGCAGCAAGAGGAGAACGUUCUUUUUCUUGAACAAGGUGGCCGGUUCCCUGGGAGAAGGCUGGGAAUGGCACGUCCGGCCAGGGCAGGCGGUGCGGCAUCCUCCUCCUGGGAUUCCUGUGGCCUCCCCUGUUCUAUUCAUUGUUUGGCUUCCCACCCAUAAGCUCUGGGAUACCCAGGGCUUGCUUCCCAGCUCUUCUCAUCUCCAAGCCUCUGCUCCCCUUCCCACCACCACUGCCAUAUAAAAUGGCCAUGCUAACUCCUACACAACUAGGAGCCUCAGCAGGAUUGCUAGGAUGUGGGUUCCUUCCUGCAUGCUUGCUUCUGCAGCUGUGUGGCCUUGCCAUGGCCCUCCCACCACUUUCCCUUCUACCUUGCCUUCCAUUGUCUUCCUUCUCCCAGAAAGCCAGGUUUCACCACGUGCUCACCACAAACUGUCUCCCCUCCCUCGUAGGAGUCACUGCAGUAGGGCACCUGCAGGCCCUGGUAGAGUGAGCAGGGCUUACGUGUACAUUCUUUCUCACUCUAAGGAUGUGAUAUCUGACCCUGAUGUCAGAGAGGAGGUCUCAGGACUAGCAUUCGGGGUCCUUUGAGUGUUCCCAGAAUGGUUUGGGGUAUCACACAAAACACCAGAGCUGAGGAUAGGGAUAGAGUCCCCAAACACACAUCCUGGGAGCAAGCCACUUCAUCUGAGCUUCCCAUACCAGGAGCAUGGUUUGUGCUUUGAUGGGAAACCUAGCAAGCCCCUGCACUCUGGGGCUUCUCCUCUCCUGGAGCCCAGGGCGGCUCUGGCCCGAUGAUAUGGCAGCCAUAGGUACAGGUAUUGCAGGUGCAGCCUUUCUUAAGUACCCUGCCUCCACUCUAUAGCCCAGCUGCUGCUGGAGUCCAGGACCUUAGACCCAGGAUGAGCAAAAGGAUCCCACCAGGUUGUCCAGGACCAUUGCCAGGGUGACCCCAGAGUUCUUCAGACCUGUGUCUGAUACUGAAUACAGUGCCAUGGGACCCUGCUCCAAUCUAACUGCCUACAACCUGCCCGUCCCCCUGCUGCAGGGAUGUUGCUGCUACCUCGGGAGGCUCUCUGAGACUGGUGUCUGGUCUUAGAUGCUGCACAUAGUACCUGGUGCUAGGGUCUAGGGGCUGCCCAAAGCCCAGCAGGAACAGCUACUACUCAUCCUGCAGAGGCCUUGGCCCAGACCAGCUUUCCAUCCAAAGCCUCACCUGGUUUCCAUGUCCAUCUCAACAGUCUGGCCUUCCUGUGACUGUAGCCUGGCAGCCACACCCUCAGUAAUCCCGCACAGUGAGUCCAGCUUCUCUGGGAGCUUGGCCUUCAGUUAGCCCAGUCCAUGAGAGGGCAGGGUAAUGAGGAGGAGUAAAGGACCUAUCUUCUCUGUCCACAUAAGGAAGUUGGGACCACAAGGUCUUUUAUCUCCUUGUUACUCCCCAACCCCACCAUAACCUCCUACUCAGCACACAGCUGUAUCCUGGUAGAUUAUAAGGUGAGCUUCCAGAACCUGGCAGGAGGCUGGUGUAUCCCCCUGCACAGAGGGAAGUGUAUCUGAAUGUUGUGUAUGUGGCUGAUAUGGAAGACAUACAUGUAUGCAAUCCAUCAGCGUUUAAAGAAGAAGAUUGGCUCCAGUUCGGAGGAGGAGGAGGAAGAUUACAGAUCUAUUCUGAGUAUUUUUUAGAGAGUUAAUAUUUAUAUUUUUAGUAAUUUUCUGGUAGAAGGAAAUUGCACAAUAAAAUGAUUUGGUUUGG